GCAGAUCCGCUGUACUUGCGUCCGCUACAGUAUGUCAAUCGCUUGCCCCAGCACAGGUAAUGCUAAAUAUGAGGCGUGCGGAGCGGUGCGCGGACCGGCAUCGGGAGGGCGUGGCCUUAGGGGGCGCCCCUGUGGAGGAGGCACCCGGAAGGUCAGGGCUACCCCGUCCCGCCGGUACCGAGGGCGGAGAGGCUCCGCAGGUCCUGCUGCGGAGUCGGAGGGUUCUGCCGGGCUGUAAAGCCAUUUUCAGCGAGGCCGCUGCACGAACUUCCGAGGGAUGUUAGACCUAGAGUUGCCGCCAGCCCCACUGAGCUUUUCUAGUUCCGUCCCGACAUGCGCGCCCUCGUUUGUGCGCACGCACGCACGCAGUACGUCGCUACGUCCCGUCUCUAGCCCUGGCGCUCCGCCGGUCCCGUUCUGCAGGUGGGCGUCGCCGCCGACUUACCAACAACCGGGUCGGGGGCUCCCGGAAGUGCUCUUGCGGCUUACUGCCUGGCACAGCUGUCAUUCUUCUCUACAGAAGAGCUUCUCCUCAUCAACUGGGGAUGAUUACAGUUCUUCCUAAAAAAGAUGACACUCGCUUUUGGAGUUGGCACUACAAGAUGCAUGAGAAAUACAGUUGAUCCUAGAACAACACAGGUUUGAACUGCAUGGGGUCCACAUAUAUGUGGAUUUUCCUCCACCUUUGCCACCCCUGAGAGAAGACCAACCCCUCCUCUUGCUCCUCCUCCUCAGCCUACUUGAUGUGAAGACAAUGAGGAUGAAGACCUUUAUGGUGAUCCACUUCCACUUAAUAGAUGGCUGCUCUUUUUCUAAAGAGGUUAACACUACAAACUGUAAAGUCUGAAAAUAGUUGCAUUAGAUGUUUUGGUAAACACAUCCUGCAAAAGACAGCACCAGCACAGUUGUCCCCUAUUGCUUCUGCCCCAAGACUCUCCUUCCUAAUUCAUGCAAAAGCCUUUAGUACCGCUGAAGACACCCAGAAUGAAGGAAAAAAGACAAAAAAGAAUAAAACAGCUUUUAGUAACGUUGGAAGAAAAAUUAGUCAGCGAGUUAUUCACUUAUUUGAUGAGAAGGGCAAUGAUUUGGGAAACAUGCACCGAGCAAAUGUGAUUAGACUUAUGGAUGAGCGAGACCUGCGACUGGUUCAAAGGAACACCAGCACAGAACCUGCAGAGUAUCAGCUCAUGACAGGAUUGCAGAUCCUCCAGGAGCGGCAGAGGCUGAGGGAGAUGGAGAAGGCGAACCCCAAAACUGGACCAACCCUGAGAAAGGAACUGAUUUUGUCUUCAAAUAUUGGACAACAUGAUUUGGACACAAAGACUAAACAGAUUCAGCAGUGGAUUAAGAAAAAACACCUAGUCCAGAUUACCAUAAAGAAAGGAAAAAAUGUAGACGUGUCAGAAAAUGAAAUGGAGGAGAUAUUUCAUCAAAUACUCCAGACUAUGCCUGGAAUAGCUACAUUCUCAUCUAGGCCACAAGCUGUUCAAGGAGGAAAAGCUUUAAUGUGUGUUCUUCGUGCUUUCAGCAAAAAUGAGGAGAAGGCAUAUAAAGAAACUCAAGAGACCCAGGAAAGAGACACUUUGAACAAAGACCAUGGAAAUGAUAAGGAAUCAAAUGUUCUGCAUCAGUAAUUUUAAUAAAGAAAAGCAUGCUCUGAGAGAAA